GAGACGGGGUUUUGCCAUGUUGCCCAGGCCAGUCUCCAACUCCUGAGCUUGAGCAACCCACCCGCCUCGGCUUCCCAAAGUGCUGGGACCGCAGGCGUGAACCAGCGCAGCCGGCUGGAAAACUGGAACUCUCAUCGGUUGAGAGUGGCAGCUCUGGAGCUCGGACUCCCCCACCUCCCCAGGAUUUGUCAUUGCUGCUGUUUGUCGUGGUUAUCUGUCAGAAAUGAGCCGGGCGUGGUGGCGCCUAUAGUCAGCUACUCGGGAGGCUGAGGCAGGAGAAUCACUUGAACUCGGGAGGCUGAGGCACGAGAAUCGCUUGAACUGGGAGGCUGAGGCACGAGAAUCGCUUGAACUGGGAUGCAGAGGCUGCAGUGAGCCAUGUUGGUGCUGGUGCACUCCAGCCUGAGCAAGACCUUGUCUCAGAAAAAAAAAAAGUUCACAAAGCCCACUGUUCUUACUAAGAUUCAGCUGUUUUUCUUGAAUAAAUGCUCCCCGUGCUACUGUAAUUCUUUGGUUAACUUUCAGAGUUCUGGAAAGUUGGCUUGGCGCUUUUCGCCGUCUCUCUCCUGCUGCCUUGGGGUCCUUUCCGUGACCGUUUCCCUCCCUGACACGUGUACAUCCCUGUGUAUUUCACAUCUCUCUAUGCUGGAAAGAGGUUCUCCACUUCUAGUGCCACACCACGGGGGUCUUUCUGGCUUUUUCCCUGUUUGCAUCUGCAGCUCCCUUCCCUGGCAGGGAGAAACCUGCCCCACUGCCCUUCACCAGUUUCUUCACUGAGUCAGCCGCCCCUUCCUAUGCAGACACCCCUCACCCCUCUCUGGCCCUGCUUCAGGCCCCCCUUCCCCGCCGUGUGGGCUUCUCGCUGUCCCCUAAGCCUUCGAUGUCCCCUCUGAGCCACCGCGGCCACGGCCAACAGGGAUGCCUCCCUCACCAGCGCCUCCUGAUAGCUCUGGGCCUGAGCUCGGUAGAGAAAUGGAAGAGGAAGGUAUAUGCAGUGUUUGACUGUCUCUGUUUCUUGUCUCACGUCACAAAACAAGACUGAAUUUGGAUUUCUGAACGCGACUGUGUUUUCCUCGGGAGUAAUGAAAUUAGGGCUCCAUUUCCUUCGCUGUUCCCAAGGGAAAGGUCCUGCUUAAACAGGUGCUUUGUGAGUGGAAACGUGGCCAGAGUGCGGCGGGUGCUUUGUGAGUGGAAAUGUGGCCAGAGUGCGGCGGAUGCUUUGUGAGUGGAAACGUGGCCUUCUCUGGAAGCCCUGGGGAGGGGCUUUCCGACUGAGAGGAAGGCCUCGCAUCUGCCCACCGCCCAGUCCUGGGCCUCACAGUGAGGAUGCAGGUCACGCUGCACAGAUGAGGCCCGUGUGGCAGGUGGUCCCAGGAACGAACUCGCCUCCCGCCAGCCCCCUGGGCCUCCCAUGGCCCCAGCCCCAUCAGGUGGAACGUGCACUGCCUGCGUUUCAGAAGGGGCGGCCUGGGGAAGGGGCGGCUUGGGCACGCUGCCCCUCACCACCACGCGUGACCCACCCAUGUGUCUCCCUUUCAGAGCGGGAACAGCUUCCACGUGUUCGACCAGGGCCAGUUUGCCAAGGAGGUGCUGCCCAAGUACUUCAAGCACAACAACAUGGCCAGCUUCGUGCGGCAGCUCAACAUGUAUGGCUUCCGGAAAGUGGUCCACAUCGAGCAGGGCGGCCUGGUCAAGCCAGAGAGAGACGACACGGAGUUCCAGCACCCAUGCUUCCUGCGUGGCCAGGAGCAGCUCCUUGAGAACAUCAAGAGGAAAGUGACCAGUGUGUCCACCCUGAAGAGUGAAGACAUAAAGAUCCGCCAGGACAGCGUCACCAAGCUGCUGACGGACGUGCAGCUGAUGAAGGGGAAGCAGGAGUGCAUGGACUCCAAGCUCCUGGCCAUGAAGCAUGAGAAUGAGGCUCUGUGGCGGGAGGUGGCCAGCCUUCGGCAGAAGCAUGCCCAGCAACAGAAAGUCGUCAACAAGCUCAUUCAGUUCCUGAUCUCACUGGUGCAGUCAAACCGGAUCCUGGGGGUGAAGAGAAAGAUCCCCCUGAUGCUGAACGACAGUGGCUCAGCACAUUCCAUGCCCAAGUAUAGCCGGCAGUUCUCCCUGGAGCACGUCCACGGCUCGGGCCCCUACUCGGCCCCCUCCCCAGCCUACAGCAGCUCCAGCCUCUACGCCCCUGAUGCUGUGGCCAGCUCUGGACCCAUCAUCUCCGACAUCACCGAGCUGGCUCCUGCCAGCCCCAUGGCCUCCCCCGGCGGGAGCAUAGACGAGAGGCCCCUAUCCAGCAGCCCCCUGGUGCGUGUCAAGGAGGAGCCCCCCAGCCCGCCUCAGAGCCCCCGGGUAGAGGAGGCGAGUCCCGGGCGCCCAUCUUCCGUGGACACCCUCUUGUCCCCGACCGCCCUCAUUGACUCCAUCCUGCGGGAGAGUGAACCUGCCCCCGCCUCCGUCACAGCCCUCACGGACGCCAGGGGCCACACGGACACCGAGGGCCGGCCUCCCUCCCCCCCGCCCACCUCCACCCCUGAAAAGUGCCUCAGCGUAGCCUGCCUGGACAAGAAUGAGCUCAGUGACCACUUGGAUGCUAUGGACUCCAACCUGGAUAACCUGCAGACCAUGCUGAGCAGCCACGGCUUCAGCGUGGACACCAGUGCCCUGCUGGACCUGUUCAGCCCCUCGGUGACCGUGCCCGACAUGAGCCUGCCUGACCUUGACAGCAGCCUGGCCAGUAUCCAAGAGCUCCUGUCUCCCCAGGAGCCCCCCAGGCCUCCCGAGGCAGAGAACAGCAGCCCGGAUUCAGGGAAGCAGCUGGUGCACUACACAGCGCAGCCGCUGUUCCUGCUGGACCCCGGCUCCGUGGACACCGGGAGCAACGACCUGCCGGUGCUGUUUGAGCUGGGAGAGGGCUCCUACUUCUCCGAAGGGGACGGCUUCGCCGAGGACCCCACCAUCUCCCUGCUGACAGGCUCGGAGCCUCCCAAAGCCAAGGACCCCACUGUCUCCUAGAGGCCCCGGAGGAGCUGGGCCAGCCGCCCACCCCCACCCCCAGUGCAGGGCUGGUCUUGGGGAGGCAGGGCAGCCUCGCGGUCUUGGGCACUGGUGGGUCGGCCGCCAUAGCCCCAGUAGGACAAACGGGCUCGGGUCUGGGCAGCACCUCUGGUCAGGAGGGUCACCCUGGCCUGCCAGUCUGCCUUCCCCCAACCCCGUGUCCUGUGGUUUGGUUGGGGCUUCACAGCCACACCUGGACUGACCCUGCAGGUUGUUCAUAGUCAGAAUUGUAUUUUGGAUUUUUACACAACUGUCCCGUUCCCCGCUCCACAGAGAUACACAGAUAUAUACACACAGUGGAUGGACGGACAAGACAGGCAGAGAUCUAUAAACAGACAGGCUCUAUGC